AUUCACACUCAGGACCUUGCCUUGAGCAGCAAACCAAACUCACUACCCCUGACACCAUGAGCUACUACGGCAGCUACUAUGGAGGCCUGGGCUAUGGCUGUGGAGGCUUUGGUGGCCUGGGCUAUGGCUAUGGCUGUGGAUGUGGCAGCUUCCGCAGACUGGGUUCUGGCUGUGGCUAUGGAGGCUACGGAUAUGGCUCUGGCUUUGGAGGCUAUGGAUAUGGCUCUGGCUUCGGAGGCUACGGAUAUGGCUGCUACCGCCCAUCAUACUAUGGAGGAUAUGGAUUCUCUGGAUUCUAUUAAACUACUGCCCCAGCAACACAAUGUGUGAAAUUAUAAGAGGACUUUCCCAGAGCUGACUUCAAUCAUUGGACAACAAAGAUCAUGCUGGAGCUAUUUGCACAAAAGAAUUUAACAUCUCAGAAUUUCAGGCAAUUUUUUUUCUCUGUAUACCCACAUCUCUAUAAUAAUCCUAGUAUUCUCUACUUUUGCUUUUAAAGCUGAUUGAAUUAUCUGUUUAUCUUCCAAUAAAACAUUCUAUUUUCAAACACAA